GCGCCUUCAGUCCGCGCGGCGACAGCGCCCGCCCGCGCCUGCCCCGGCGUGCUGCCCCGCGGCUUGGCCCCGCUCGGCCCCAGGUCGUGCCUUCCCUCCCCGGCGGAGGCCCCUGCGGACUGCCUAGAGCUGGGUCGCAACUGAGGCGUUAUCCGCGGGCCUGGCCUCGGGAAGUGGCGGGGAGGAAGAAGAGGCGGCCGGGACGCGUGACAGGAGCAUUCGGGAAGAUUCUUACGGUGCCCUUCACGCGGUGCCUAUGGACGGAGAAAGCCGCCGCAAAUAAAACCAUCCCCCAGAGUAGUUGUGGCGGAAUAAUCUAAAUAUGGGUGUUGGAUUGAGGAAACUUGAAUAUUUUUGUAUCCUGAAGGGAGAAAUGGAUGAAGAAGAAAUGGAUGAAGAAGACCGAAGAUAAUGAUGAAGGGAUAAUUUGGAAUAGGAUUCACAGCAAGAGAGACAGAAGGGAAAGACAUUGAAGAAACAGACUAGUUAACACAUGAAAAAAAUAGAGCAGAGGAAAACACGUCCAUGUUUUUCCACGUCUAAUGAGAACAGGGUCCUAGCACAGUGUCUGAUGGAGCUUUCCUACCAGACCCUGAAAUUCACGCAUCAGGCGCGGGAAGCGUGCGAGAUGAGGACAGAAGCACGACGAAAAAAUCUUCUCAUUUUGAUUUCGCAUUAUUUAACACAAGAAGGGUAUAUCGAUACAGCAAAUGCUUUGGAGCAAGAAACUAAACUGGGGUUACGACGGUUUGAAGUUUGUGACAACAUUGAUCUUGAAACUAUUUUGAUGGAAUAUGAGAGUUAUUAUUUUGUAAAAUUUCAGAAAUACCCCAAAAUUGUCAAAAAGUCAUCAGACACAGCAGAAAAUAAUUUACCGCAAAGAAGUAGAGGGAAGACCAGAAGGAUGAUGAACGACAGUUGUCAAAAUCUUCCCAAGAUCAAUCAGCAGAGGCCCCGGUCCAAAACCACAGCGGGGAAGACAGGGGACACCAAAUCGCUCAAUAAGGAGCAUCCUAAUCAGGAGGUAGUUGAUAACACUCGCCUGGAAAGUGCCAACUUCGGCCUACAUAUAUCAAGAAUCCGUAAAGACAGUGGAGAGGAAAAUGCCCACCCACGAAGAGGCCAAAUCAUUGACUUCCAAGGGCUGCUCACAGAUGCCAUCAAGGGAGCAACCAGUGAACUUGCCUUGAACACCUUCGACCAUAAUCCAGACCCCUCAGAACGACUGCUGAAACCUCUGAGUGCAUUUAUUGGCAUGAACAGUGAGAUGCGAGAAUUGGCAGCCGUGGUGAGCCGGGACAUUUAUCUCCAUAAUCCAAACAUAAAGUGGAAUGACAUUAUUGGACUUGAUGCAGCCAAGCAGUUAGUCAAAGAAGCUGUUGUGUAUCCUAUAAGGUAUCCACAGCUAUUUACAGGAAUUCUUUCUCCCUGGAAAGGACUACUGCUGUACGGCCCUCCAGGUACAGGAAAGACUUUACUGGCCAAAGCUGUGGCCACUGAAUGUAAAACAACCUUCUUUAACAUUUCUGCAUCCACCAUUGUCAGCAAAUGGAGAGGGGAUUCAGAAAAACUCGUUCGGGUGUUAUUUGAGCUUGCCCGCUACCACGCCCCAUCCACGAUCUUCCUGGACGAGCUGGAGUCGGUGAUGAGUCAGAGAGGCACAGCUUCUGGGGGAGAACAUGAAGGAAGCCUGCGGAUGAAGACAGAGUUACUGGUGCAGAUGGAUGGGCUGGCACGCUCAGAAGAUCUCGUAUUUGUCUUAGCAGCUUCUAACCUGCCGUGGAAGAAGCUGUCCUCCCUGCCUGCAAUCAAGGUCUUGAUUGUGCCUUCACUAGAUCAACAUUUUUCCAAAAGCAGUCUGCCACAGGUCAGCAAGCAUUGUGCAAAAAAUGAGAUCUAGUGGCCUGGUAUGUUCAGGAGAUACCAAGUUAAAGACAGUUCAACUGGUUUCCCCCAGCAGGGUUGCUCAAUGUCUUUAAAAUACGACUGUGGGCCAGGUGCAGUGGCUCAUGCCUGUAAUCCCAGCACUUUGGGAGGCGGAGGUAGGCAGAUCACUUGAGGUCAGGUGUUCAAGACCUGCCUGGCCCACAUGAUGAAACUCUAUCUCUACUAAAAAUACAAAAAUUACCCAGGCGUUGUGGCACGUGCUUGUAGUCCCAGCUACUCAGGAGGCUGAGGCAGGAAAAUGACUUGAACCUGGGAGGUGGAGGUUGCAGUGAGUUGAGAUUGCACCACUGCACUCCAGCCUGGAUGACAGAGCAAGACUCUGUCUAAAAAAAAAAAAAAAAAAAAAAAAAAAAGCCUGCCUCUGGACUCUUGUACUCACACUUACCUGAGUCUAGAAUCUGGAAUGCAGUGGCACCCCCACCACCGUCUCCCUCCCCUUCAGAUAUCUGCAGGGCUCUGUAGGUCACCUUCAGGGGUCUGCUCUGAUGCCACCCACUCAGCAUCCUAUUCAUAAUUGCAGCCCCGGCCCCAGCUCCCUAUGCUGCAUUCUUGCUUUGUGUUUCUUCCUGUGCUGUUACCAGAAGUGAUACUAAUUUGGAAUUAAUGGCGAUUAAGCUUUACAGCCCCUUGAUUUCCUGGGACCCUUCCUUGGCUCAUGGAGAGUCCCCAGCAAUGUCCUCAUGGUCUUCAUUUUUGCAAAAUUUGUGAAAUGGUAGUUUUAUUGCUGGAACCACUUUUGCAAAAAUUAUAUAACAGUUAGAAGAUUAUGGCAGUGAAAGAGAUCUGAUCUAACCAACCUCCAUCUUGCCUUUAAUCAUUCCUGGGCUCAAGCCAAGCUAACUUUGGGAGACAUUUCGUUUAUAGUUUAAAUGAUAAUAACCCUUUUUGAAAACUAUGUGGCCUUCCUAAAGCUAAUGCAAGACCACCAGGUUAGAAGGAUGAGAGGAGCCUGAAGUCGUUAACUUCCCCAGUUACUCCUGGAGAUAACAUCACUAUUGUAGAAUCUAAGUAAGAUUGGCCUUUAGAGAUGUCUUUUAAAGUUUUUGCAUUUCUGAUGACCCACGACUCCACGUGAACCCACCAACUAGUCCCAUGGCCGCCCCCAGAAGAGGACUACUUUCCAUACUCCCAUUCAAUUGCCCACCAAACUAUCCUUGAAAAAGCCUAGCCUCCGAAAUUUGGGGGAGAUUGAUUUGAGUAAUGACUCCAUUUCCCAUGUGGCGUGGCCAGGCUUGUGUUUAUUCAACUCUUUUUUUAUUGCAAAUAAAUAAAUAAAUAAAUAAAAGAUACUAUUUGCAGGCUGGGAAUGGUGGCUUAUGCUUGUAAUCCCAGUGUUUUGUAAGACUGAGGCAGGAGGACUGCUUGAGGCCAGCAUGGACAACAUAGCAAGACCUCGUCUCUACAAAAAAAUUGUUAAAAAAUCAGCCAGGCGUGGUGGUGUGUGCCUAUAGUCCCAGCCACUCAAGAGGCUGAGGCAGGAGAAUUGCUUGAGCCCAGGAGUUUGAGGCUAAAGUGAGCUAUGAUCACACCACUGCACCCCAGCCUGGGCAACAGAGCUGCAACACCCUGUCUCUUAAAAAAAAAUGCUAUUGUGCUUUGUGACUCUCUAUGAAAAAUAAGAUAAAGCAGUACUUUCCACACUUAUCUGACCCCACUCCUUUCCUCAAGGAGUAUCUCACAAGUCUAGUGUUCCAUUUGAAAACCUUUUGGAAGACAUUAGUUUGUAUUACCUCACCCUGAUCUGAUGAAUGCAUUUUUCAUUGCAAUUGCCUUCAGUCCUGCCUGUAGGCUUUUUUUUUAUUUGGAGACAGAGUCUCGCUCUGUUCCCCAGGCUGGAGUGCUGGAGUGCAGUGGCACGAUCUCGGCUCACCACAACCUCUGCCUCCCGGGUUCAAGCAAUUCUCUUCCUCAACCUCCCAAGUAGCUGGGAUUACAGACACCCACCACCAUGCCCAGCUAAUUUUUUGUAUUUUUAGUAGAGGUGGGGUUUCACCAUCUUGGCCAGGCUGGUCUUGAACUCCUCACCUCAUGAUCCACCUGCCUCGGCCUCCCAAACUGUUGGGAUUACAGGCGUGAGCCACUGUGCCCAGCCUGUUAUUCAUCUUUAAUAGUAUUUUUGUGCCUACUAGUGGUCAAACCAUUUUGCUUGGAAUUACUUACAUACAACACUUCACUAUCCCACACAAUAAUAUCAAGCCCAUGAUCUUCCAUGUGUGUUUUACGGGUAAAACCCAUAUGACGAGGAAAGAAGUAUACUGUGCAGGAUUUGGUAGGUCCAGUGGGGAAGGCACAUGAUGACUAGCAGGAGGUUACUAAGCAGUAACCUUGCUCUUGCUUCGUUCACACCUUACUGUUUGAUCUCAUCAGACAAAAACAACUUUCAACCUGGUUAUUCUGGCAUUACCUUUUCUUCUUCACAGGGUGUAGGUUGACAUGCGAAUCAUACAUUUCAAACCACAUUUAAAACAUUAUAAAAUUAUUAUAACCAUUUUAUAGAAAAUAGGAGAAUUAGAAAAAAUACUUCUGAUUUCACCACUGUGACUCAAGUAUUACCAUCUUUGUAUCUACCUUUCUGGUGAAAAUGGUUUAGUUAUUUAUCAUCUUUUGCUUCCAUAUCCUUCUCUGGUAAUGUUUUUUGUUCCCAAGAGAAAAACAGUUUUUACUCUUUUGGUUAUUUUAAAGUAAUAGUUGUUUAUUAUAAAAAUCAUAAUUUAUAUGCUUUAUUAUUAUUUGAAAGUGAGUAGUCUUCACAAUAGCAAAGACAUGGAAUCAACCUAAACGCCCAUCAGUGAUAGACUGGAUAAAGAAAAUGUGGUACAUAUAUACCAUGGAAUACCAUGCAGCCAUAAAAAGAACGAGAUGAUGUCUUUUGUGGGAACAUGGAUGAAGCUGAAGGCCAUCAUCCAUAGCAAACUAACACAGGAACAGAAAACCAAAUACCUCAUGUUCUCACUUAUAAGUGAGAGCUAAACAAUGAACUCAUGGACAUAAGGAGGGGAACAACAGACCCUGAGGCCUGCUUGAGGGUGGAGGGUGGGAGGAGGGAGAGGAGCAGAGAAAAAUAACUAUUGGGUACUGGGCUUUGUGCCUGACUGAUGAAAUAAUCUGUACAACAAACCCCCAUGACAAAAGUUUACCCCUGAACCUAAAAUAAAAGUUUAAAAAAGUGAA